ACUGCCCCUCGACUCCUGUUCCGUUGGAGGGGCCUGAGGCGAGCCUGAGCGCGCUGUUGGCCGGAGGGAAGCCGGAGGAGACCGGGUCGACUGGGCAGAGCGGCAGAGGGUCGAGGAGCCUGCUCUGCACGCCCAGGGAGUAGAAGUGGGCAGGGAGCAGGGUCACGUGAGGGAGCGCGCCGCGACUGAGCUUGGGUCCGACUGGAGCUCAGGCUCGCGACCCAGACUGGUGGGCCAGGCCUCCAAGCCGGCCUUACACCCAAUCCAAGGAGGACAGACCGGACACAGAGGGACGGAGCGAGCAAGGAGACAUGGCUUCAUCAUUCCUGCCCGCGGGGGCCAUCACCGGCGACAGCGGUGGAGAGCUGAGCUCAGGGGACGACUCCGGGGAGGUGGAGUUCCCCCAUAGCCCUGAGAUCGAGGAGACCAGUUGCCUGGCCGAGCUGUUUGAGAAGGCUGCCGCGCACCUGCAAGGCCUGAUUCAGGUGGCCAGCAGGGAGCAGCUCUUGUACCUGUAUGCCAGGUACAAACAGGUCAAAGUUGGAAAUUGUAAUACUCCUAAACCAAGCUUCUUUGAUUUUGAAGGAAAGCAAAAAUGGGAAGCUUGGAAAGCACUUGGUGAUUCAAGCCCCAGCCAAGCAAUGCAGGAAUAUAUCGCAGUAGUUAAAAAACUAGAUCCAGGUUGGAAUCCUCAGAUACCAGAGAAGAAAGGAAAAGAAGCAAAUACAGGUUUUGGUGGGCCAGUUAUUAGUUCUCUAUAUCAUGAAGAAACCAUCAGGGAAGAAGACAAAAAUAUAUUUGAUUACUGCAGGGAAAACAACAUUGACCAUAUAACCAAAGCCAUCAAAUCGAAAAAUGUGGAUGUGAAUGUGAAAGAUGAAGAGGGUAGGGCUCUACUUCACUGGGCCUGUGAUCGAGGACAUAAGGAACUAGUCACAGUGUUGCUGCAACAUAGAGCUGACAUUAACUGUCAGGACAAUGAAGGCCAAACAGCUCUACAUUAUGCCUCUGCCUGUGAGUUUCUGGAUAUUGUAGAGCUGCUGCUCCAGUCUGGUGCUGACCCCACUCUCCGAGACCAGGAUGGCUGCCUGCCAGAGGAGGUGACAGGCUGCAAAACAGUUUCUUUGGUGCUGCAGCGGCACACAACUGGCAAGGCUUAAUCAAAAGACUGGAAAACUGCAGUCUGUAAUAGCAUAAGGCUUCCAUUAUGAAAGAAAACUACAAAAAUAAUACUUCUUUUCCACCCGUCUUUGACAGGGUCUCGCUAUGUCACCCAGGCUGAAGUGCAGUGGUAUGAUCAUGGUUCACUACAGCCUCAACCUCCUGGGCUCAAGGAAUCCUCCCACCUCAGCCUCCUGUGUAGCUGAGAUAGCUGGGACUACAGCUGAGUAGAAUCCUGGGCCCAAGGGGAAAGGACAGGAAAGCAAUGGAACACCGACUGCGGAGCUUCCAUUUGUUCUCCUGAGUGAGUCUUGCUUACUUCUUUCUGGCUAGUGAUAUCUUUCCUUUAUUCUUUAAGCAGCUGUCUUUUUGGAAAACCACUGUCAGAAAGAAAAUCAGACUGCUCAGGUGCCAGUCUCCAGUGACCAAACUAAAAUAAGGGGGUUGUUGUUGCGGGGACCAGAUCUUCUCUCCUUUGUGAGCUGCAGCCAUUUUAUAAUCCCAAAAAGUUAUUACUAGGUUAGCAUUGUGGUGGAAGCUGUGUACACUAGAGGAUAAAGUGGAAGCGGUCCAAUGAACCUGCUAUACUCAAAAACAGUUGAUAGUAUGUUGAAAAGAAAGAUGCAACAUAGGCUGGUGAUGAGGGGCUGAGAAUGGAAGACAAGUUAGGCUACCCAAAAACAUGGUAUAUAGUGCAUAAACUAGCCAAAAUUCUCAUGCCCAUUACCAGUGCCUCAGCAAUGAGUAACCAAGUUUAGGAGCAACAGAGCCCUUCCUAGCCACAUUGUGAAUUUCCCUAACCACCACCCAAGAGACUGGGCUAGUGAAGAAAAAAAGACCUUAUGUACAGCACCUUCUGUAUUCCCCUACCAAUAUCUUCACUCCCAUUUGAACUUCUCAUCUUCUCCACCCUUCCUUGGUAUAUAACCCAGUAAGAUCUCUUGCCUUUCUCAGCCUAAUAAAGCACUUAACGCGGGAGAUGAUUUUGGCAAAGGGUCAUGACUCUCCUUGAUAGCAGAGGGGGUCUCCACUAAAAGACCUUUAAUCCCUCCAAGAAUCCCACUGGGCAUUCUGCCUGGGAGGUACUAACUUUCCGGUUUAAGUGGGUAGACUUUAGGGGACAAAGCAGUUGUAGGACUUAGGUUAAGUCACAACAACCCAGUGGCAGCAUUAGAGAACUCAGAGGUCCAGAGCCCAACCUCCUGCUUUGUACCUAAGUAAAUUGUUCUAUGUAGUGCAUUUUUUUUUUUAAGUUUUCUCUAUCCAGGAAAGGAGAAAAAACAAAGGGGGAGAGGGAAAUGCCACACACACAAUAAGGUGGCAGAGAAGUUGGCACUGCUACUGUCUAAGGAGUCUCAGAAUAUUUCACCAAGUAUUCCAGGAUAACUAAUAGCUAAACAUGUGAUGAAUGAGAUUUCCUUGCCCACUCUCCCUAACAAGACUCUAUGAGCACCGUCCAGUAGAGCCAUCUGCAAUGAUAGAACUGUUUUAUAUCAGUGUCGUCCAAAUACAGUAGCCACUGGUCACAUGAAGCUGUUGAGCACCUAAAAUGUGUCUAGUGUAAGGAACUAAACUUUUAGUUUUAUUUAAUACUAAUUUAAAUUUAAAUAGCCAUGUGUGGCUAGUAGCUACCAUAUUGGACAGUGCCACUGCUUUGGAUCUUCUCUUCAGCCAAACAAAACUAAUGACUAGUGGGGAAAAGAAACACGCUGUAGUUUUUCCACAGUGGAAUCCCAGCUGUAAAGAAAUGCUAUGACUUUUUUUUUUUUUAAUGUAAUGAAAAAGUCCCUGUUGCUGUUUCCAUUCCAGCUAAACUUAGGGUCUGCACACUAAUAAAGACUCCUGCAGAGAAAACAAACCUAAAUGGAGAUUCUCCUGGAAAAUGUUUGUCCAGGAGCCCUGAUGACUCUGAUGAGGUGUUUCUGUCCCUCUGUAAAUAUAGACAUUUGCAUAUACUUUCUCUAGAAAGAAAAAUGUAUGAGUGUGAAGGACUUUUAAAAUGCUACUGGACAGGCCGGGCAUGGUGGCUCACACCUGUAAUUCCAGCACUUUGGGAGGCCCAGGUGGGCGGAUCACUUGAGGUCAGGAGUUCGAGACCAGCCUGGCCAACGUGGCAAAACCCCGUCUCUACUAAAAAUACAAAAAAUUAGCCAGGCGUGUUUGCGCAUGCCUGUAAUCCCACGUACUCUGGAGGCUGAGGCACGAAAAUCACUCGAACCCAGGAAGCAGAGGUUGCAGUGAGCUGAGAUCACACCACUGCACUCCAGCCUGGGCAACAGCGCAAGACUCUGUCUCAAAAAAAAAUUUUAAAAAUGCCACUGAACAAACAGGAACUAAAAGUUAUAUGGUCAACAUUUCUACUGCUCAUUUCCUAAGUCUGGGGGCAGAGGAUCGUGCCCAGGAAAUGACUAUUAGAAAAACCAGGGAACUUCCUCUAAUCAGUCCUUUAUUGAGUGGUUCUGGUAUUUCAUGGCUCUAAGUAUAAUAGUUCUGGCAUUCAGAGUUGUAUAUUUGGUUUCCUUCUGAUGAUAAAAGGAAAGGACCUCACAUCACUCAGUUUUUAUUCUAUUUAUGUCAAGAGAAAAAACUUCCAGCAAACCAAAUGAAAAGCAAGACACAUCAGCAUCUAAAGAAUUUCCAUAUUUAUUUUACAUAAUUUUACCGUACACAUCUCAUGCCAACACACAGGAGGCAUAUACAAACAAACGCACCAGCUUCUGUUUUCCAAAGUCAUAUGGCAAUAAAUAAGGAUGGGUGGGUCUUUUUUUUUUCUUUUUUUCUUUUUUUUCCCCAGGAAACGAGACUUCAUUUCUCUUUAACUGUACAAAAUUUACAUUGUGAAGGAUGAGGGCAACGAUCCAGAGCUGAGGGGAUCUGGGGCUUUGAGGUCUGAUUGCAAGCUCAGAGCAACUUCUGGAAUCCCGCAGCCCUGAACCUGCUUGUUUGGCCGAACACAGUCCUCAAGUGGGAAAGUUGGUGUGAUUCUUGCCUCUCGGUGGGCAAUAGAUGAGAGUGGGGGUGUCCUUCCUCUGUUCACCUGUGCUCUGCCUCCCUAAGCAAAGGAAUGCUUGGUGCACCUCCCAAACCUGCAGCUGUCUCCUUACCAGAGCUAGCAGCAUGAAACUGUGCUUUUAGUGUGGUCCUACCAAGCAGAGUGUGGAUGGGAUGGCUUUGCUGAGCUCUCUCUUUUUGGCUCCAGUCACUCACUGUUUAGAACAGUUGGAGCAACUACUGCAAAAAGGGCCAAUUGACCAAUCCAAGAAAGAAGAGAGCCAGUGAUGUGCUUUUCAUUUAGCUUUCAGCAUGCCCAGAGCCCUUCAGCAGCAGGCAAUAAAACAAAACUCAUUUCCGCUUAAUUGAAUUUUUCUUCAUCUCACGGUUUCCAAUUUUUAAAGUGCAGUGUUUAAAAAUGAGCCUCCUCAGGCCUUCCAGACCCUGCUGGCUGGGGAGGUAUGGUCAUUAUUUUCAUGGUUAUAACCAAGUUGUCAGUCGUGGCACGUGGAAGUGUAGGUGCAGAGAGUGGACUGUCAUACAACACACAGCCUUUGCUCAUCAGAAGCCUUGAGCCCCCUCCUGUAAAGAGGCAGUUGGAAAUCACCAGUUUGAGCUUCUGAGAUAGGAAUGUCUUUUGUUUUACAGAUUUCUUACACUUCCUUGCAAAGUGAGUUUAAUGAUGAAGAUCUAAUGGCCCAAUUAUCUUACUAGGUUUCAUGUUUUACACUGCCCCCCCCCAAAAAAAGUUUAAGGACACUGCCAAAUGGUUUUCUUGUGGCUUAAUUUUUUCCUCUUUCCCUGAUGUUUCACAGUAUUCAUUUGCAGGAACAGUGUUAUCAAUGAUAGUUGAUCUUUAUUUUACGUUAUAUUCAUAACUGUCAGAUGAGACAAGAAAGAGAAAGCACAAAGACUGAGAGGAAUUUGCCUGAGGUUGCAUAGCAAGUCCUUGAAGGGCCAAGAACCUGACUCCCAACACUGAUUUACCCAUCGGGCCAGCUUCUUAGCCCUUAAAUCUGGUAUUUCCUCCAUGGUUUCAUUACGUUCCAACAAACAGAGAUUCCUCCAUAGCCCCUCAGUUUCCAUUUUGCUUAUACCAGUUACCACUGGAACUUGGGGUUUUAACUAAUUUGCUCCUGGAUUCAAGAGCUUCCUACUCUAAAGUCGACCAGCCAGGCACUGCAGAUAAUGGUUGCCUCUAGAAGGUCUCAUUUCAUUUUUAAAAUUCAUCCAUGUCAUUUUAGCAAGGGGGGAAACAGCUACCAUGUAGCACCUUAUACCCCAUAAUAGACUUCCAAGCAACAGAGGAGUGCCUCUAAGAGAAGCUAAAAGUAAUGAAUGCCCGGCUUUUCUCCAUUUCCAAACCCCAGAAGAGUCCUGUCAUGCAAUGGCUCAUUAGUGGCACCAGCCCACCCAUAAUGCUAACCCAACCUGUAGGGAGAUCCAUUUAAAAUCUUAGACCUACUGUGGCUGUGCUUCUAAACAGGCAGCAGUGUUUGCUGCUUUCUGGGGAGGUGGCUCUGGAAAACAAAGCUCUCCUGGUUUUCAGGCCAGUGCUCUCAAGGGUUUUUCCAGCUAACCAGCCCUACUGAUGCCAAAGAACUAUUGACCUCGUCAACUGCUCACUGAGUUCCUCAAGAGAUUUAUUAUAUUAUUAGUAUAAAUGAGGAAGGCCUCUCCUUCCACUAUUGAACUGGGAAUUAGUAUGAUUAACUUACAAAAACUGGUCAACUUACUUACAGUGAUCUUAAACAGUGCUACACAGAGGAGGAUGCCCCCCCCCCUUUUAAAAAGCCUGCUCUCCCCCACACUAUACUCACCAAAAACUUCAAGGGCCUCUGAAAUCCCAUGAGUUGCUAAGCCAAAUAGUCAACCUGCAACAGUGAUCUGGGUGGGCAGCUUUUCAUCUGGUUCAUUGCCCAGCAGAGCCUUUUCUCCUGUGUAUUUUAAGCAGCCUGCUAAGAAGGGUGUAUUUAAAAAGCCAUCCUCCAAAAAGACGACUGCAUUUUCCUUUCCUCACAUGGCAUUUGUGUCUUCCUCCCCACCCCAGUGUUCAUGAUUGGAGAAUUCCCAAUAGCACAGAAUUGGCUAGGAUUAACACAACAUCAUCCAUAAACAUGGAACCUCAAGAGAAGUGUCUAUGUUUGCAGACUUCUCAAGCAAAAAUCAUGACCACUGCAGCACACCAAAAAACGAGGGUACGCUAUAAAAUUGGUCAGAGAAGAGGGCCCGAAGGCUGAUCCCGGAAUUUACUGUUUUAAAGAACUUACUUAAUUGAACUUAGUUUAGUCCUGGAAAAGGGCUUACAAAAGAUGUAGCAGUCCAAGAGGAACUGUGUAUUCUUCCUUUAGUCUGCCUAUGACAUGCCUAAGUCUUUGCAGUCCUCAAAAGGUGACCAACCAUUCGUAGAAGGAAGGGUCCUUAGGGUCUCUGGCCCCAUCACUUCAUGUGAUAGGCAAUGCCUUCUCACCCUUUCCUACUCUGCUGAUCUCAUUUAAGAGAAUGGGAGGCCAGAAGAAGCAAACACAGCUUCCCAGAGGGACAGGAAUAAAUUCCAGCUGGCUAAAUUCCAGUUUGCACAUGGAGAGCUUCCUGAUGGUAGAUGGGUGCACAAGGUGGGUGGGAGCUGCAGCACCAUUCAGGACAGCGUUUCCCACAGCAGUGCAGUCUGUCGCAGGAGUGGCAACUCGUAAAGCGGGGGUUGGCCUUGCUCUGGCCUCAGGCUUAGUGAUUUGCUACUGCAAACCUGCACAACGGGGAGUCCCUGCACCACCACUGGCCAGAGAGUUCUGGCUUUCUGACCAUGGGACUGCAGCCCAAGGCAUGGCAGGUGUCCAGCCAGCAAUCCAGAGAGAUGCAGCCCAAGAACCACUUAGAACCCUUUGGACAAUUUUAGGGCUGCUCCCUAAAUUACUCUUCCCAACCAAGGUAGGCCAAAAAAAAAUUGCUGGUUCCUGGAAAUGACCAAAACUGUCCUCCAAUUGAGUCAGCUAGGACAGCAGAGAAAGCUUUCAGAGGGGUAGACUUGCAAGCUCAUCUAAACCAACUCCUUCAAAACAGACUCCAAAUAUUUCACCCUACAAGGGAUGGGGAACUCUGGAAGACUGGCAUCAGCCGAUAUGGCUGAACAGACUGCAGGUUUGGAAUCCAAAUGUGUCUACAAAUGUUCACUGAUUGAUUGUCAUUUUGUUCUCCCCACAUUUUAGUUUUGCUCAUUUUACAGCCCACAGCCUGUCUUGUGGAAUAAAUGAUACAAGCAAUUGAAGAAGGCACACUGUGCACCAAGGGGACGACUCAGGCAAUCUGCAGCGGUGGUCCAGGGCUACUCAGCUCAGCCUCAGUCACCUGCAAUGAAAACCACCUCUUGCCAUCAGAGUCAAUGAUAUAGAUGGGACACUUAAAAACCAAAACAGGUUCAUAUUCUCUGGUUUGUAGGAAAGAAUUCAUAUCUUCACAGCAAAAAUAAAAAAGGAGGGGGCAUGUUUUUAAUAUCAAACUGGCCAUCAAAGUGUUCACUGACCUUUAAUAACUGAUCUUUUCAUUUUGAAAUAUAGGGUUCAAUAAGGAUGGUCCAGAAAUCACUUUUAUUUUACUCAAGGGCUGUGAGGCCUCUACCUUAGGAGUCUCAGUUCUGGUGAGAGCAGUGUUUUGGGAGGCAUUGUGUGAGACACACCAGUUGGAGCAAAGUUCCCAAAGGCCAAGGGGGCCUAUCACAGUCACCUUGUGCUACCAAAGCACUGAGCAGCCAAGCCCCUAAGCAGAACAGCAGGGGAGAGACCCAACAAGCCAGUGUCCCUAGAGCUCUAGGCCAUUACCCCCUGUGCUGUGUUCUGAGAUGAGUCUGCUCUCCCACUGCUUCCCCAGGGAAACAAUGCCCUAGUGUGGUCUCACAGCCUUCUAGGAAUCAGCGGAGGACUUCCAUUGAAAAUAAUGGAAAUUCACAUUGGCGUACUUUCGAUCCUUAAAAGGCAAGUCUCUUUUGAUCCUUGAAGAUAUUCUCUCAAGCCAGGGGGGCAGGUAGGGUGGGGAGGAGAGAAGUUUAAAAAGGAGGAUGAUCCAUUUCAUCGAGCCAAGAGCCUGGGCUAGUUGGAAAGUCGGGAUAGCCUACACUGCUUCCUGUGGAGAUGUCAGAGGUGGGUCCCCCAGCCAUGGCUCUCAGCGUCUGGCUUACUCCCUGCCCUGCAUGCGCAAUGAUGCCCAAAUUACUGUCCACCGUGUAAUCCAGCCCAUUGAGCAAAGGAGCGUGGGAUGGCAGGGACGAUAUGGAGGAUGGAGACUGGGGGAUUCCAUAGGGGCUCCCAUCCCUCAAGUCCUGAUAGGAUUGUCCUGUCCCGUCCAUGGAGAAGCUCCCAUUCAUUAACUGUCCGCCUGUAACGUCCCCCACGUUGCCAUAAAUCCUAUUGGUGUGGCCAAGUUCUGAGAGAAUUUGAUCCUCUGUGGACAAAAGAACGGAGAUUUAUUGUCAGCUGCCAGGACUCUGAUGGUCCCCUGCUCUUCACAACCUAGGAACACACAUGACCAGGAAAGAUGCCCAAGGAUGGCAGCUGCCUUGCAGCCAAGCAUGGGUCAGACACACCAAUAUGGCAGCCUGAUAUCCAGAGGCCAACCCAGGCCAAGGAGAAAAACAAGAAACACCUGCAAAGACUAAAUUCCCAGGUCCCAGAAGGAUGGACAAAUGUUUGGUGAGCUCGUUGGUCCCUUGUGGCUCGUGUACUAAUACUCUGGCUACACUGAGGAGGAUGAAUGCCUAAGGCUGGGUGGGUCAGAUGUCUCCACAUCACAAAUGGAAACUACAUGCUGACAACAUUUACCCUGAAAGCUUUCAAGCUGAGAAAGGGCUUGGUUUAGUUGAUUGGGAAGCAAGCAGGCCCAUAUGGUCAGGGAAGCUGAGGACCACUCUUAGACAUCUGUACAAAAUCCUUCUGGUCUAUCUGGAAGAGAGGUUCAAUAUCAAAGGACUUGGUUUCUGUCUGUAUUCAAUAAGCUCUUCACUGGGGACAAAGAAUUGACUUGAUUAAGGCAAAUGAACCUUCUUUUUUCUUAAAGAAUUUCAUUAAGGGGAUCUAAUGGAAUCUUUGCCACUUGAAAGAAUUUCUCUCUCCAACAGAGGUGAGCAGUUUUAGUCUUUGAGAAAUUAUUCCCAGAGAAACCAAUGAUAGGUCAGCCCAGGGACCCACCUGCACCCAACAGAAAUGAGCUUAACAAUCCAGUAUGUUCUAGGUGUUGACUUCAACAGCCCAGAUGAGAUUGACUUUCCCAAUCCUGCCAAGAAGCCUAAAAGGUGAGUAUUAGUCCCAUGAGCUGUCCCCAAGGCCUCACGGGCCCUGUGUUCUCAGAGGAGGCUGCCCUCUAGGGCUCAGCUGACCUCUGGGCUGAACUAGAGUCCUCCCAGGGCAUCGUUGUCCUGGCAGGCAACUUGUUCCAUCCUCUGUCCCACAAACUUCCUUUUCUAUUUCCACCUGGGCCUCUGCACCAAUCCCUAAAUAAGGCCUCCCCAGACUAGACUUCAACACCCCAUCCCUUCUGAGGCCUGCCCCCCAUUCCCCUUAUGAAAAAACAUGGUGGGGGGAGCUCAUGCUCUUUAAAGGGAGCAGGAAGAUGAAGGCUCCACUCCAUUGUCAAAUGGCCAUGAGUUAGCCUUUUCCCUAUACCUGUCAUCCCAAAUGACCAGGGCCCUCUGCGGGAGCCACACGCUCCCUGUGGGAACGAUCAUGCCUUCCAGGUAUACAAAUGUGCCAGGCUUUCCCCAAGCACAUCCACAGUUGGUUGUGUUCAUUGAUCCCCACAACGCAGUGAGAUGGGCAAAGAUAUGGUAUUCCUCUUGGGAAUACUGGGGCUCAAGAGAAGUGAAUCGAUUUGACAGAGCUGCACUGGAAACCAGGUCUCUGAUCGCCAGUUGAGUACUCUUCCCUUUCCCCCUCCGCAGAAGACCUUCCACAUUUGAGAACUCAGUACCUGAGAACAGUUAUGAUUCUUUGCAAACAACCUGAGGAUUCAUAACAUGCAGUAAUUUACAAUUUUGCUGAUGCAUGAAUUUGAAUAUAGUGCAUGCUGCAAAGCUUGUGUGCAGGGGACAGAAUGAAGUGAGUGGUGGGGAAAGGGAUUUCGGAAGUGAAGCCAGUUCCCCAUCUCACAUGCACUCACAGUACUGAUUUCCCAGGAAAAAACCUGUGGAGCAUGACCUCCCCACCACCAGGACUGGAGGAAGGGGUGGCUCUAGGGGACUAUGGGAGUAGGCCAGUGUCCCAGCAAAGGGGACAAAGAUGGGAGAGGGGCUAGGGGCACAAGGCUGGAACCCAGUCAUCUGUUCAUAGCUGUGUGGGCUGAUGAGGGAGGCCCCAGUCAGCAGGAGGGGAGGGGAGACCUUGGGGCCACAGGACGGGGCCUGGCCCAUCCCAGCUUCCAGACCUCAGCAAUCUUGUUUCCUACUCCUGUCCCAUGGUAAAGGGCCACUACCAUUUCCCCCACCCUUCACUGCAAGUCUUAAGGAAAAGCCUGUGUUCAGGAGGGAGUUGCCAAGGCCUCAAGAAAGAUCCCUCCUGAGUGCCAGGGAUUACAGAUUCCCAGGGGACUUUCCUAAGGCCUCGGCCUGGCCCCUCCAGCCCUGCUCACCUCGGAAGCUCAGCUCACUGUCACUAACCCCACAGUCCUCUGCAGAGCUCUCCUUCUCCUGCUUGCUGCUGCCCCGGCUCCUCUUGACGCUCUUAUAGAACUGCCCCCAGCGGUGCCGCCCUGCAUCCUUCUUCAGGCGUUUCUCUUUGGCCCUUCUGUUCUGAAACCAAACCUGCCACACAAGCACAAGGGACAUACUCAGGGGGCGUCCACCACAAACCCAAAGCCCCCAGGACCCCCUAGGCGGGCGGCUGGAAGCAGACUGAAGCCUGAAUGGAGCACAGGUCUGGGAGUGCGAUGCGCCCCACCCCCUCUCCCCAGGUGGGCCUCAGAACUCUGUCUUCAGUUCUGGCAAAAGCCCUGGGGUCAAGCCCUGAGCCCAACCACCCGUGAGCUGAUGUCACUCAGGAUACCUUCCACCCCUGUCCCGGGCCUGGGAUCCCCGGAGGGCACAGGAGUGCUGGCAUCUCACCUGUACGACCCUCAUGUCCAGGCCUGUCUCUGAGGACAGCUGCUCCCUCACGUGCCGGGCAGGCUUGGGGGAGUUCUUGUAUGCAUUCUUUAAUGUCUCCAGCUGCUUGGCUGUGAUGGUGGUCCGGGGCCGCUUAGCUCCAGCCUCUGAGUCAUCUGCAAGGAAAAACCACUGCUUACUGGCUUCGGCCUAUCUGCAGCAGCUGCGCCUCCUCCCACACCCUCCCUUCCAUCCUUUCUGCACCUAAGCCUGCCUGCUGUAGGCAGGACAGCGCGAGGCACAGGGGACAUCAGAGUGGAGAGGUCCCCACUCUCAUGGCACUGACUCCUGCACCACGGGCCUUCCCAAGCCACUGAAAAGUGAGGACAGCAGUCCUUUCUCUGCUCAGCUCCCUGCCUCAACCCUCCCCUGCCAGCCCAGCUGCACAGAAGUCUCAUCAGAUUGAAUGUACCCAAUUCCACACGUCCCUGUCAUGACAAACACUCUGCUCACACAUCCUCAUGAGUUCUUGCCAGAGCUGUGAAGGUGAACAGCCAGGUUGAAGUCAUGUUCAAAGUCGCCCCAGAUGCCCUCCCCUCUGUCUCAUCAGGAGUCUCCCAUUUCCCCACAGCCAUGUCACCUUUGCCCUGGCGUCGCUGGGCUCACAGCCAGGGGUGAGCUUGCACACCCAACAGUGUCUAAGCAGGUUUCUAAACUAUAGGUCAGAACCCACUCGUGGGCUGUAAAGUCACCUUAGUGGAUCAAAACUAAAACAGGAAAUCAGAUGAAGAGAAUGGGAUGGAAUGGCAAGAUCAUUUCAUUAAACUUUAGUUUUUAUUGUAUAAAUAUGUGUACUGAGAUGAAAUGUAAAAUGAGUUUUACUGUGGAUUGUAGUCAAAAUUUUUUGAGAAAACUAGUCUAAGGAAUGUUCUGGGCAACACACUGACUGAUCAACACAAAGUCCUAGACAGAUUUUGAGUGAACAAGCUCAAGUUCCUGUUAGUUAAAGUCUGGUUUGUUCCAUUCAAAGUCAGGUACAGAGAGAGGCGCGUGCGUGUGUUCGGAAGCACAGGUGAAUGUAAAGGUUUGUUUCCUCUCCCAGCACUUAGGCAUACUGCCCUUUUCUCCACAGUGCCCCUGGAGGACACACGGAAUAAAGUCAGCAGCUGGCCUGGGCAGCUCUGCUCUCUGUGCUUGCUCACCUGUGUGCCCCAGAAGGUGUCUCUGUGACAUUCCUGACUUCCUCUCUGUCUUUUCUCCUUUCUUUCCAUUCAAGAAAACCCUCUCUUAGAAACAAUAGUAGCCAACAUGUGUUAGCACCUACCAUGUGCUGGUGUUGACUAAGGACUUUAUAUGCAUUCGGUCCUCACAAUCUACAAGGCUCUCCCUGGAGUCAGCAGACCUGGCUUCAGUGUUCUUGAUGAGUGAGUGACUUGGGCCAGUAACUCACUUCCCCCUUGGAAGUCCAGAGGGCAACACGGCCUGCCCUGAUCUUGGGAGGCACUAGAGGAAUGAAGCAGCUGUGCAGCCAGGACAUGUGUGUACACAGUGAGGGGGGACACACCCGUGCCUUCCCUUCUCCUCGGGCUGUUUUCUUCUCUCACGUGGCCACUGUCAUCCCGGAACUACUGUGGCCCAACUCCCUCCCUGAAGCCCUGAACCCGAAGGGUAGGGAUUCCGGAGCCCCUGCCACAGAGACUACACUACUUAGAGAGUCAUUCCAAAAGACAAAGGGGAACCUCCAAAAUGCCUUCCUUUUCAUUCUGAGGAGUCUGUCCCUUCUGUGCAUAUUUAUAGUCUACACGGGAGUGUCUGAUGCAACUUUGAAUUAUGCAAAUGGGAAAUAGUGCACUUGUGUACAAUCUUUAUAUUAAAAAAUGUGAAAUAAUGCAAUCACCAAAAA